GACAACGCGGCGGCUCACGAAGGUUCCAUUGUUAUGCUAAACGGGAAAGUGGAGACCGCGCCGGCGUUGCCUAGAGAACGCCUGGACUCAGAGUAGCAAAAUGGGCCUCUCCCCAACUCCCCUCCUCAUCCCCCAGCACAAGGCAAAGGGCACCCCUUGCUGUGAGUUUGGGGGCACCGGCUGUCGGGGGCCGACCCAGAACUUUGCGGGGUCCCCUGAGGGACCCGUGGCGGGACCGGCCCCGGGUUCGUCAAAUUCCGCCGAUGCUUUCAGGAGGCUGAUUAAACAAACGACAAGAUUGGAGUGGGAAAUGAGAGGCUCUUAAAAGUGGAAGCUUUUUGUUUGUCCAUUUACAAGAAAUUGGACAAUGAAUCACUUCAGGAAGAUGGAGGUCAUCAACCUCACCACCCUACCUAUGAUACCAGUGGAUGAGCACCUGGCUGUCUCGCUUGUCGCACGGAAUACAAUGGUGAAGACUGUGAGGAAGGAGUUAGAGAACAAUCCACCCUCAUGCCUUAUUGGCUCCAUGCACCAGGUGAACCAAAAGAUUGCUGACAUAAAUCUGCGUACCGAGCCGUCGGCCAACAGCCUGGCAAUUGAGAGAUUUGAGUUGGAGAAGAAGGCUUUAAGAGAGAAAACUCGCAGCAGUCCAGAAGACAAAGGCAAAAACCUUUCCCUCAGCCUUGAUGCUCUUUUCAUGGGUCAAGAGACAAAGGAAAUCUCAGUAUUCCUGCAAAGGCUCCGAACUCAGACAUGCCAGAUCUUCUGUUAUAAAAAGGAAAACAGCAGAUAAAAAUCUGCUGGCAGAGCUGUACCAGUAUUCCAACUUCAACAGCUCCAAGCCAAACAAGCUUCCGAAUGGCGUGGACUUCUGUGACAUGGUGGGCAACGUGGUCCGGGCUGAGAGAGACUGCCUUAGUGGCAAGCAUUUCUGUUCAGGUAGAGAAUUAGAGAAGUUUCUCUCUUCUUCUUCUCCAAGAGCCAUCUGGCUGGAUAGCUUUUGGUGGAUAUUUCAUGAGAGGUACCAGCCAAACAAGGAGCUCCAGAAUAAUCUGUUUGACCGGAUAGCCCAGCACUAUGCCUUACUUUUGUUUCGUGUACCCAAGUCCCACUCUGAAGAGGCGCUCUUAAAAAGGCUGCCAUCACUUCUCAGCAAAGCCGUGUACACCAGCUUCUGUUGCUGCUUUCCACAGUCCUGGUUCGACACGCACGAAUUCAAGUCUGACAUCUGUAACACAAUGAGCCUGUGGAUUUCAGGCACCUAUCCUAGCCCACAGAGCUAUGACAGCUGGGACUACUCGGAACUAGACCCAGAGCGAUUCCGCAGAGAAGAAUUAAUGUUGUACAGAAGAAGACUGACAAAGGGUAAGAUAGCAGGGAGAGAGUUUUCUUUGUUUGCUGGUAAGAGAGCCUUCUCCCAGAAGCCAGCCCAGAGCAGGAAAUUCUACCACCCUCAGUCUUCUAGUGCAAAUUCACCCAGUGAAAAAACCUCUUCGGCCAAGCAGAACUCAGAAAAAAGCUUACGAAUGCAGAAUACUGCAAAAGAGCAUCAUUGUCAGACCCUGGUCUUGAAGAAACCUACGCAAGAAGUCAAGAGGAUAUCAGAAGCAAGAGAAUGUGAGAAUAUGUUUCCUAAAAAGUCGUGUGCUGCCUGCAAAAGCCCUGAGCUGACUUCAAACCUCUUCAACAUUUAUGGGAAGAGCCCUCUGAUUGUGUACUUUCUCCAGAACUAUGCCAGUCUGCAGCAGCACGGCAAGAAUGUGUUGAUAGUCAGAAGGGAAAAGACCACGAGCACCCCUGACUGCACCCCAACGUAUACUGAUGUCAUCAGCGAGACCCUGUGCAGCAUGAAGAAGCGGAAAGACAACCUCAAUCAGUUGUACCAGCAUCAUUGGACUGAAUGGAAUUAUUUUGACAAGCAUCUAAAGGAGCUGCAAGACAACUUCUCCAGGGAAAUGAAGAAUAUUGAUCCAAAAGCAGCAGAUACAAAAAAGGCAAACCACAUGUUCAUCCCACCUUCAGCCGUCAAUGAGGAAUCACCUGACAAGAAAACUAAGGGAAGUCUCCAAAGAGAAAUUGAGUUUAAGGGUUGUUCGAACAAAAACCAUGGGAAAGGUAGAAGUGUGAACAUGAGGGGAAAGGAGGAGAGGGAAAGAGAAGAGAAACAGAAGUUGAACAUUUCUUUCCACUCACUUCCAAGCCCUGAGGAGCUCCACAACCUAGAACCAGGAAGCGCCUACAGAAUCCGUGAUAUUUCUGCUACGAGGUGGAGUGGAACAAGAAAAUAAGAAAAUUGUGGCCAAAGACAGAAAUAGGAAUCAUGAUUUCUCCAUAGGGGAAGGAUUCCGUUGUAGUUUUUCCUAGGCUGAGUGAAAAGCAGGAGUAGAGAGUUGGUGCUUGGGUCACUACAUUUAUUCAUAGAUUUACUCUUUCAGUAUUUUAUUACGUGCAUGCUGGUAAGUAUGUUACAAAUAUGACCUCAUACAAAGGUAAAACUUUCAUACCAGCCGUAUGAAGUAGGGAUUAUCCACUGCAUUUUACGCAGCAGCAAGCCCAGGUUUAGAAAGGUUUCCGAAGUUCUCUGCUGUAGACACUGGGUAAUUAACAGUAGAUAAGACACAGUCCCUGUUCUCAAGGGAGUCACCAUCUGGUAGAGGGAAGACAGAUGUAUCAACACAUUAAAUGCUGUAAGUAUUGGACAGAGGAAAAAGAGAAAAGUGUUGUGAGGGAAAAGGAAAAUGGGCCUAGAGGAGUGCAAUUUUUUGUAACAAGCUUUGUGGAACUAUUAAUUUGAUAAUUUGAUAGGCGCUUCUAUUAUGCUGCCUCUGAACCUUUGCCUCCUGCUCCUCUAACCACUGGGAUUGCCAGCCUAUUUCCAAUAUGCCCUCUUUCUGCCUGGCAAACAUCUUGUCUUUUCUAAACUCAGCCCAGGGACAUGACAUCUGUAAUGUGUUUCUGUGUGACUCCCAGGCUUCUGCCUUCUUAACCUCUCACCUUCCAGCUCAUUUGAGUGAAUCUUUGUCCAAGAAUUGAGAGAAACUUUAUAGGUAAAGCAUGCACAUGUUGUCUGAUUUAAUCUAAAAUAGAAAUAAGAAAACAAAAAAUAAUACUGCAACUAGGGACACAUUUAGUCACUCCCAGUUCAUGAGACAAGGAAUAGUAAAGUUCAUUCCUACCAUAGCAAAAGUCAGGAUUUAAAUGUAAAUUAAUUUUUUUAAUUAAAAAAUUUUAAAUUAGGCCAGGCGUGGUGGCUCACACCUGUAAUCCCAGCACUUUGGGAGGCUGAAGUGGGCAGAUCACGAGGUCAGGAGUUCGAGACCAUCCUGGCCAACAUGGUGAAACCCCAUCUCUACUAAAAAUACAAAAAUUAGCUGGAUGUUGUGGCGGGCACCUGUAAUCCCAGCUACUCGGGAGGCUGAGGCAGAAGAAUCGUUGGAACCCAGGUGGCGGAGGUUGCAGUGAGCCAAGACCAUGCUAUUGCACUCCAGCCUGGGCAACAAGAGCGAAACUCUGUCUCAAAAAAAAAUUUUUUUUAAUUAAUUUUAACUAAAUUAAAUUUUUUAGAGGCAGACUCUCAGUCUGUUGUCCAGGCUGGAAUGCAGUGGCGCAGUCAUAGCUCACUGCAACCUCAAAUUCCUGGGCUGAAGCAAUCCUCCCACCUCAGCCUCCCAAGUAGCUAGGACUACAGGUAUGCCACCAUGUCUGGCUAAUUUUUAAAGAAAUUUUUUUGUAGAGAUGGGAUCUCACUGUGUUGCCCAGGCUGGUCUCGAACUCCUGGCUUCAAGUAAUCCUCCUGCCUUGUCCUUCCAAAGCACUGGGAUUCUAAGUGUGAGCCACCACACCUGGCCUGGAGUAUCUAAUAUUGUAUAACAUAAUAAUAGUAAUCAUAGGUGAUGUCAUUUAUUGAGUACUUAGUAUGUGCUGAGUGCUCUGCUAAGUCUGGUUUAGACAUUAUCUCAGUUAACCUUCCUGGUGUCCCCCAAGAUGGAUAUUGUUACCUCCAUUUUCUCCUAGGAAGAAACGGACUUGGGGGGGAUGAUUAGGUAUUUGCUAGAUGUCUAUUCUGUACCAUCCCUGCACUAGGCCCUGUGAAUACAGAGAUAAAUAAAGACACAGUCCCUGACCUUAUGGGGCUCACAAUCUGGAAAAAAGAGAAGGAUGUGUAAACCAAUAAAUGCAUUAAUGCUCCGAUAGAAAGCUGCGUGGAAUCUGAGAAAAACCAAGGCAGAUGAAGCCAGUGUGCCAGCAGCCCUUUGGGACAGAAGAUAUUUCACUGAGGGGCACAGGCACAGGGGUUGGUUUGCCAAAGGACCAGCAGCUGGGCUGAAGGGCAUAGGUUUUAUCAUUUGAGCUUCAAGGCACAAGGCAGUGACCUGGUCUGUGCUAGAACAGUUCACCUGUCACAGCCAAGAGGAAAGAAAUGGUGCAGAUGGCUGUUUGCCCAAACCAAGCAGCAGAUAAGCAGAUCUUGGGAAAUGUAGCUCAUCCCUCAGACACACAUCUUUACUUGAAUCCUGAGUAGAACUCUAGGUGACCCCCUUGGAGGCUAUUACUCAUGUAAAAGGGGAUGAAGGAAAGGUAAGAGAGAAGGAGCUUAGGCUUUGGCAUGAGAAAAUUUGGGCCUUUGAAUCCCUGCCCUGCUUCACCAUAUGGAUGUGUGACUCAGCAUAGUAGCUGUGCAUCUUGACCUUUCUGAACGUGCUUUCUUGACUGCAGAAAGGGAAUGCCUGCCUAGGAGGGUUGUUGUGAGGAUUAGAUGAGAUAAUUUGUGCAAAGUUCUUGGCACAGUACUUUUCACUUUGUAAUUGCCACAAGCUGUUAUUGUUGUUAUUGCUGUUAUAAAGUGUACUCUUCUUGGCCGGGUGCAGUGGCUCAUGCCUGUAAUCCCAGCACUUUGGGAGGCCAAGGCAGGUGGAUCGCCUGAGGUCAGGAGUUUGAGACCAGCCUGGCCAACGUGGCGAAACUCCAUCUCUACUAAAAAUACAAAAAAAUUAGCCGGGCACAAUGGCAGGUGCCUGUAACCUCAGCUACUCAGGAGGCUGAGGCAGGAGAAUCACUUGAACCCGGGAGGUGGAGGAUGCAGUGAGCUGAGAUUGCACCAUUGCACUCCAGCCUGGGUAACAAGAGUGAAACUCCAUCUCAAAAAAAAAAAAAAAAAAGUAUAGUCUUCUGAAACCAGAACGUGUGAGCACCUGCCGAGUACAAGGCACCAUGUGGGGCAGAUAAGCAGAACACUCUCUCACCUUCCCUUUACUACCCCAGCCACUGUCAACUCUUCAUUUGCAGUUUCUCUAGGAACCACACUUUCCUAUUUCUGGAUCUUUUGUCUGUUGCUGCUUCUGGACCUGAAAAUGCCUUCUCCUCCCUCCUCUUUGUUAACUGCCAACAUCACUAAUUCCUGCUCUUCCUCCAGGACCCCGCUUAGACGUCCCUCAUCUUGGGAGCCUUCCCUAAUAUACCAGGAGCAAGGUAGGCACAAGUGCUCCACUGCAUUAUGCUCCAACAGCAUUCUGUGCCAUCCCAUUAUGGCAGCAGUUACCAUAGUAGAUUGGAAUUGCCUGUCUACCUAUCCACCGCUACUAUUAGCCCCCAUACAGCAAGAAGGUCUCCUUAUUUUCUAAGCCCAGGACAAACUGCAUUUCUGUCUGUCAGGACCAUUUGUUGCACAGUCCAAGAUCAUCCCUGCAUGGACCCUUUCCAGAAAUGACUGAGGACUCAGAGUUGUAGCCUCUCAGGAUGUUAAAUAUGAAGAAACCUGUCUCUGCCCUUUGUAAACAUUAGAAGGGAAAAUUAUGGGGAAGAAUUAUUUGCCCUUUAUAAGGGAAGCGGGGUAGAGCAUCAAAGGGAACUAACAUUUAAAAAGCAUUUGCUGUAAUGUGGGAUAAAGCAAAUGAGUAAUUGUAUGAUAUUCUAAUUCUGUCAUUCCCAGUGUUGCUGAAAACCCAUACUCUCAGCAUGGAAGAAGAUAAAUUCAGAUGUUAAACUAGAAGAGAUGAAGUUAAAAUCCUAUAGUCCUGAUUUUGAAUUGCUUAUGAAUUGAUGAUGAAAUGUAUGUUUUAGAACAUACAGUUUCCUGAAGAACAGGAGGGAUAGCUGGAGAGGGGAUAGGAGGGAAGCUGGAAGGGGUUACAAAGAGGCCCAAAUAAACUUUUGGGGGUGACAGAUAUGUCUACUAUCUUGAUUGUGGUGAAUGGCUCAUGGGUGUAUACACACCUAAAUACACUUUAAAUGUGUGCAGUUUCUCAUAUGUCAAUUAUACUUCGAUAAAGCUUUGUUAAAAAACGAACAGGCCAGGCAUGGUGGCUCACACCUGUAAUCCCAGCACUUUGGAAGGCCAAGGCAAGAGGAUUGCUUGAGGCCAGGAGUUUGAGACCAAACAGGACAACAUAGUGAGACCUUGCCUCUACAAAAACAUAAAAAAUUAGUCCGAUGUGGUAGUGCAUACCUAUAGUCCUAGCUACUAGGGAGGCUGAGGUGGGAGGAUCGCUUGAGCCUGGGAGCUUAAGGCUGCCAUGAGCUGUGAUUGUGCUACUAGACUCAGCCUGGAUGAUAGAGCAAGACUGUGUCUGGGAAAAAAAAAAAAAAAAACCUGAGCCAGGUGCGGUGGCUAACGCCUGUAAUCUCAGCACUUUGGGAGGCCGAGGCGGGUGGAUUGCCUGAGACCAGUAGUUUGAGACCAGCCUGACCAACAUGGCGAAAUCCUGUCUCUACUCAAAAUGCAAAAUUAGCCGGGUGUGGUGGCAGCUGCCUGUAGUCCCGGGUACUCGCAAGGCUGAGGCAGGAGAAUUGCUUGAACCCAGGAAGCGGAGGUUACAGUGAGCCAAGAUCAUGCCACUGCACUCCAGCCUGGACAACACAGUGAGACUCUGUCUCAAAAAUAUGUGUAUAUAUUUCCUAAAACUCUGUCCACUGAAAUGACCUAGAAAUAAAGACUGACCCGGCAGCAGUGACCCAGACUGUGGUCUUGAAAUACUAUUUGCCCUAAAAGGAUCUAGGGAUCCUUGAAGAAAUGAUCAGUUCCAGGUCUAGGGCAGGAAAAUCAUGAGACCUGAAACAUCUUAUCACACUUAACACCAAGGAAGCUAUCAAAGACAAGGAUCCUGUCAGAAAGACUUGGGAGCAAACUUAGAGACAAUCCCAUUAGCUAAAAGAGAGGACCAUUUGGGCAUUAAUAAUAAUUGCCAUAUUUGAAGCACGUCAAACGUGUUCUCACCUGUAAGUUCAUAUUGUGACUUUUAAAAAACGGAUUGGUGUCUGGACGCGGUGGCUCACGCCUGUAAUCCCAGCACUUUGGGAGGCCGAGGUGGGCAGAUCACCUGAGGUCAGGAGUUUGAGACCAGCCUGGCCAACAAGGCAAAAUCCCGUCUCUACUAAAAAUACAAAAAUCAGCCAGGCGUGGUGGUGCAUGCCUGGAAUCCUAGCUAUUCGGGAGGCCGAGACACAAGAAUCACUUGAACUUGGGAGGCGGAGGUUACAGUGAGCUGAGAUCGCACCACUGCACUCCAGCCUAGGUGAUGGAGUGAGACUGUCUCAAAGAUAAAAAAGGAAAGGGGAAAGGAGGAAACUAAUUGGAUACUAGGAAACUUCCUCAUUAUUUUGAAAAUUGGUAAGUAAAUGAAUAAGCAUUUAUCAUGCCAUUCCCAUAUGAACUGUAUUACCAGGUAACCAAAUAGUAGUGGAACAGAAACUUGUCUUUAGAAACAAUCCACCUAAUAAAUUCAGAAAUAAUGAUAGACUUAAAAUAUCACCAUUUUGAAACCCCUAAUGAAUUAAUGGAUCUAGGUUGAUUAUCCAUGGCUGCUUACAUCACAAAAGACAAACAGCUAUUAAAUGCCUUUUGAUACUAGACCAUAAGACCACCUAUCAAAUAGUCUUACAAAUAAGUAAACUUGAAUGUGAUCUGAACUCUAGAUCCAACCACCAUAACAGGAAAUACAGAGGAUGGGGACAUCAUGGCAAAUGGUAAAUGACACCUAGGGGAUGCAAUCAGCAAAAUCCAGGCCAUGGAAAACUCCAGGGCAAAUGACUUCAUUUUUUUCAACAAAUAAGUUUCAAGGGAAAAAGAGAGGGGGAAUAUAUAGAUUAAAAGAGACUUAAAAGAGGACAUCGGUUGCCGAGCAUGGUGGCCCAUGCCUGUAAUCCCAGCACUUUAGGAGGCCAAGGUGGAAGAACCCCUAGAGCCCAGGAGGUGAGACCAAACCGGGUAACAUAGUGAGACCUUGUCUCUACAAAAAAAGUAAAAAUUAGCAGAGCAAGGUGGCAUACGCCUGUAGUCCUAGCUACUUGGGAGGCUGACGUGGGAGAAUUGCUUAAGCCUGGGAGUUGGAGGGUGCAGUGAGCUAUGAUCAUGCCACUGCACACUCCAGCCUAGGUGACAGAAUGAGACCACAUCUCUAAAAAGAAAAAAAAAAGACAUCAAUCAAUUACAACAUGUGGACAUUAUUUGGAUCCCAUUGAAACAAAAUGUGGCAUUUAUGAGACAAAUGGAUAUCUGAAUCUUAAAUAUUUUAUAUAUAAAAUUAUUCUAGGCGUGAUAAUAGCAUUAUGGUUAUAUUUUUUAAAGAGUUAUCACAUUUUAGAGAUAUAUACUGAAAUAUUCACAGAUGGAAUUACAAGAUUUAUGGAAUUUGUACUCAAAUAAUAUGGGAGAGAGAAAGUGGAUGGAGGUAUAGGUGAAACAAGAUUGACCAUGUGUUGAAAAUUGUUGAAGAUGGGUGAUGGGAAUAUUAUACUGUUUUACUUUUGUGCAUAUUUGAUUUUAGCCAUAAUUUUUAAAAUUAAAGGCAUCUACCAUGGACACUUCUAAGCAUAUUUUACACACUUUCAUUGUGGUCUCACUAAAGCCCUGUGAAUGAGGUACAAUUUCCCCCAUUUUCAAAUUGAGGCUCUUCUUGUUUAAAGCACCAUUACUCCUGGCUUGGGACUUCUGUUAUACAAUAUUCUCCUAGCAUUCUCUUUGCCCUUUCUCUUGCCCCUCCAAUCAGUUCUCCACACAGGAGCCCACAUACUUCAUGUGUAUUAACCCAUUUAAUUCUCACAACUCAGCGCCGAUAUUAUUCUUGGUUUUCAGAUACCGAAACUCAGGCACAGAGAGGUUAAAUAAUUUUCCCAAGACCACACAGCUAGUGAAUGGCUGAAGUGUGCUCUAUGUCUGGCUUAGUUGCUGCUCCUAUGUGUACUUAUGACAGGAAAAUAAAGUCAAGAUAUGAAUAUACAAGCCUGCCAUAUAGUGGUUUAGCAUGUCAGUUAAGAGCAUGGUCACUGGAGCCAGACUGUGAGCCUCAGGCAAGUUACUUAACCUCCUGGUGCCCCAGUUCCAUCGUGUAAAUAGGGGUGAUAAUUGUUGUGCCUCAUGGUGUCUGUGUGAGGAGUGGAUGCAUGAAUCUGUGGGAGGCACUUAGAACAGUGCCUGACACAUGGUAAGUGCAGCAUGUACUGGCUAUCAUGAUCAUUAUUGGGUGUUCAACAAAUACUCGUUCCUUUUGGCCUCUCUCCUUUAAUUUUGAAAUUAAAAUCCUCCACCAGAACCACUUGCAGUUCCCCAAAUAAGCCUCUGUGUUCCUUCUGCCUUUCCCGCCCUGCCCGAUUGACAAAUCCUCACUGAUCCAGCCCCAAGCUAAGGGCCACCAUCCCCGCAACCCCAGAGAGAGCCUCUGCUUGGUUCCCAGCUGCAUGUCUAAUCCCUCUCAUCCUGCCUUGUGUGGUGAUUAUCUCUUUCUGCAUUGUCUUCUCUACUAGACUCAUGGCUCCUUGAGGGCAGGUACCUACCUGUCUUUAUAUCCAGCAGAGACGUGGAAUUGAGCAGUGUUGAAUAAAUGCUAGUAAAAUAAACUGUCAUAGCAAGCCUCUCUUGGACACCUAUGUGCUGAAGUUAAAAAGUUUUUCAAAUUUGGACUGAAAAAAUGAGAAAGCCCAAAAUGACUAUUAAAUAUACAUGUAUGUGUGUGUAUACAUACACACAGUCAUGCACCACGUAACGAUGUUUCAGUCAGCAGCUGACUGAAUAUAUGACGGUGGUCCCAUAAGAUUAUAAUGGAACUAAACAAUUCCUAUCACCUAGCGACUCUUAGCCUUCGUAAUGUCAUAGCGUAACGCAUUAGUCACGUGUUUGUGGUGAUGUUGGUGUGAACAAAUGUACUGUGUUGCCUGCCAGUCAUAUAAAAUAUAGUACACAAUACUGGGGUAAUGGUAAUAAAUGACUGUUACUGGUUUA